GUGCACGCGGUUGUAGCUGCCCGGCGGCGGCAGAAGCGGCGCUCGCGCCAAGGGACGUGUUUCUGCGCUCGCGUGGUCAUGGAGGCGCUGCCGCUGCUAGCCGCGACAACUCCGGACCACGGCCGCCACCGAAGGCUGCUUCUGCUGCCGCUACUGCUGUUCCUGCUGCCGGCUGGAGCUGUGCAGGGCUGGGAGACAGAGGAGAGGCCCCGGACUCGCGAAGAGGAGUGCCACUUCUACGCGGGUGGACAAGUGUACCCGGGAGAGGCAUCCCGGGUAUCGGUCGCCGACCACUCCCUGCACCUAAGCAAAGCGAAGAUUUCCAAGCCAGCGCCCUACUGGGAAGGAACAGCUGUGAUCGAUGGAGAAUUUAAGGAGCUGAAGUUAACUGAUUAUCGUGGGAAAUACUUGGUUUUCUUCUUCUACCCACUUGAUUUCACAUUUGUGUGUCCAACUGAAAUUAUCGCUUUUGGCGACAGACUUGAAGAAUUCAGAUCUAUAAAUACUGAAGUGGUAGCAUGCUCUGUUGAUUCACAGUUUACCCAUUUGGCCUGGAUUAAUACCCCUCGAAGACAAGGAGGACUUGGGCCAAUAAGGAUUCCACUUCUUUCAGAUUUGACCCAUCAGAUCUCAAAGGACUAUGGUGUAUACCUAGAGGACUCAGGCCACACUCUUAGAGGUCUCUUCAUUAUUGAUGACAAAGGAAUCCUAAGACAAAUUACUCUGAAUGAUCUUCCUGUGGGUAGAUCAGUGGAUGAGACACUACGUUUGGUUCAAGCAUUCCAGUACACUGACAAACACGGAGAAGUCUGCCCUGCUGGCUGGAAACCUGGUAGUGAAACAAUAAUCCCAGAUCCAGCUGGAAAGCUGAAGUAUUUCGAUAAACUGAAUUGAGAAAUACUUCUUCAAGUUAUGAUGCUUGAAAGUUCUCAAUAAAGUUCACGGUUUCAUUACCA